UGUGGCAUACCUUGUGUUUAGUUCAAGAACUAUAAUCUAGAUGUAACACCUGAAAAUAAACUCUUUUAUUGAUAUUCUACAGGCAGAAGAAAUGAAGAUAGCAAACAACACAGUAGUGACAGAAUUUAUCCUCCUUGGUCUGACUCAGUCUCAAGAUAUUCAGCUCUUGGUCUUUGUGCUGAUCUUAAUUUUCUACCUUAUCAUCCUCCCUGGAAAUUUUCUCAUUAUUUUCACCAUAAGGUCAGACCCUGGGCUCACAGCCCCCCUCUAUUUAUUUCUGGGCAACUUGGCCUUCCUGGAUGCAUCCUACUCCUUCAUUGUGGCUCCCAGGAUGUUGGUGGACUUCCUCUCUGAGAAGAAGGUAAUCUCCUACAGAGGCUGCAUCACUCAGCUCUUUUUCUUGCACUUCCUUGGAGGAGGGGAGGGAUUACUCCUUGUUGUGAUGGCCUUUGACCGCUACAUCGCCAUCUGCCGGCCUCUGCACUGUUCAACUGUCAUGAACCCUAGAGCCUGCUAUGCAAUGAUGUUGGCUCUGUGGCUUGGGGGUUUUGUCCACUCCAUUAUCCAGGUGGUCCUCAUCCUCCGCUUGCCUUUUUGUGGCCCAAACCAGCUGGACAACUUCUUCUGUGAUGUCCGACAGGUCAUCAAGCUGGCUUGCACCGACAUGUUUGUGGUGGAGCUUCUGAUGGUCUUCAACAGUGGCCUGAUGACACUCCUGUGCUUUCUGGGGCUUCUGGCUUCCUAUGCAGUCAUCCUCUGCCAUGUUCGUAGGGCAGCUUCUGAAGGGAAGAACAAGGCCAUGUCCACAUGCACCACUCGUGUCAUUAUUAUACUUCUUAUGUUUGGACCUGCUAUCUUCAUCUACAUAUGCCCUUUCAGGGCCUUACCAGCUGACAAGAUGGUUUCUCUCUUUCACACAGUGAUCUUUCCAUUGAUGAAUCCUAUGAUUUAUACCCUUCGCAACCAGGAAGUGAAAACUUCCAUGAAGAGGUUAUUGAGUCGACAUGUAGUCUGUCAAGUGGAUUUUAUAAUAAGAAACUGAGAAGGAGGAAUUCUGGCUGGAAUUCAUAUCAUUCAUUUAACAAGUCCUGUUUUUCACUGGUACCUCCCAUUUGCCAGGUACCA